AAGGCGGCCCCGGCGCUGGGGCUGCGCGGCAGGCGGAGCGGCCGCGGGCUUGGGGGCUUCGCCGGGGCCGGGCGGCCGGCGCCCCCGGCUGCUCCCGCCGCCGCCCGGACCCGCGCCCCGCCGGGGCAGCGGUGGUGAGAGCCCCGACUCCCCGGACGCCGCCCGCCGUGCCAUGGGGUUCCCGGCCGCGGCGCUGCUCUGCGCGCUGUGCUGCGGCCUCCUGGCCCCGGCUGCCCGCGCCGGCUACUCCGAGGAGCGCUGCAGCUGGAGGGGCAGCGGCCUCACCCAGGAGCCCGGCAGCGUGGGGCAGCUGGCCCUGGCCUGUGCGGAGGGCGCGGUUGAGUGGCUGUACCCGGCUGGGGCGCUGCGCCUGACCCUGGGCGGCCCCGAUCCCAGAGCGCGGCCCGGCAUCGCCUGUCUGCGGCCGGUGCGGCCCUUCGCGGGCGCCCAGGUCUUCGCGGAGCGCGCAGGGGGCGCCCUGGAGCUGCUGCUGGCCGAGGGCCCGGGCCCGGCAGGGGGCCGCUGCGUGCGCUGGGGUCCCCGCGAGCGCCGGGCCCUCUUCCUGCAGGCCACGCCGCACCAGGACAUCAGCCGCCGCGUGGCCGCCUUCCGCUUUGAGCUGCGCGAGGACGGGCGCCCCGAGCUGCCCCCGCAGGCCCACGGUCUCGGCGUAGACGGUGCCUGCAGGCCCUGCAGCGACGCUGAGCUGCUCCUGGCCGCAUGCACCAGCGACUUCGUAAUUCACGGGAUCAUCCAUGGGGUCACCCAUGACGUGGAGCUGCAGGAGUCUGUCAUCACUGUGGUGGCCGCCCGUGUCCUCCGCCAGACACCGCCGCUGUUCCAGGCGGGGCGAUCCGGGGACCAGGGGCUGACCUCCAUUCGUACCCCACUGCGCUGUGGCGUCCACCCGGGCCCAGGCACCUUCCUCUUCAUGGGCUGGAGCCGCUUUGGGGAGGCCCGGCUGGGCUGUGCCCCACGAUUCCAGGAGUUCCGCCGUGCCUACGAGGCUGCCCGUGCUGCCCACCUCCACCCCUGCGAGGUGGCGCUGCACUGAGGGGCUGGGUGCUGGGGAGGGGCUGGUAGGAGGGAGGGUGGGCCCACUGCUUUGGAGGUGAUGGGACUAUCAAUAAGAACUCUGUUCACGCAAGCUGCUGUGGACCUGGUCUCCUGUGUCCAGCCCAGCCUUGGGCCUGCCUCGCAGCUGUGAGGAUGGCUCCAAUUCCUGCCUCCUGGCGGGAGACUGAGGCUCAGGGGAAUGGUAUCUUGUUCAAGACCAUUUGGCAACUGAGAGGGAGAGCAGAUGUCAGGAGGAGCUACACCCACAUUCCGGGGAGGGGCCGCUGCUGGGUGGGGGGCACGUGGGGACCUGCACUCAUGCAAGCUUCUGCUCUGCUGCACCCACCAGCCCCGUCCUUGCCCGCACCCUUGCCUGCUUCCCUGGCUGGCUCCCACUUGCCUCCCGUGCCAGGUGCUUCUGGGGCUCAGCAGGAGAGGAAAGGGGCAGAGGGGCAUAGGGUCCCUCGGGUACGGUGGGGGCAGGCGGGCGCACAGCGCUCCGGCUCUGAGCCAGGCCUGUGAGGGAAGGGGCUGCAGGCUGGCAGGGUGCCGACUUCCCCCAUGGCUGCUGUGAGCCCGCAGAGUCAUCCUUGGCCCCGUCCCGCCCUUGGGGAAGAAUGGGCCCCUCUGUCCUCAGGCCCCUUCGACGUGCUGAGCAUCCAGACGUGGCGAGGAGCCCGAAGGGUGUGGGGUCCCCUCUGCAGGGUCCUGCUUGUUGCCUGUUUCCGGCGGGCGGGGUGCACAAUGGGGUCUCUAAGGACCGUUUCCCGCCACUGGCCCCAUUGUCACUGUCUCCGCCUUCCUCCUCGGCCUUUCAGCCGCAUAAAGGGCCAGUGAGGUUUGGGACAGCCACAGCCCAAGGCUCCGAGGCUAAAAGCCCCUGGGUGGGGGUGUUCCAGGACACCUGGCCCUGUGUGAGCUGCCUCCUCUCACCCCAACCCCUCGGAUCCUGGGAAAGAGACAGCCAUGGCUCAAGGGCCAGGGACCCCUGGGCUGAGCCCCAGAAAUGGCUUUCCAUUCUCGCCUGGGCCGGGGUGGGGGUGGAGGCCAGAGGCCCUGCCCAGGCAGAUGAAGCCCCCAGCUUUCAAGGGGGAAACUGAGGCUGUGUGAGGGACACAGCUGUGCAGGGCCCACAAACACGGUCCUUUCUCUAGGUUAGCGGAUGCAGAUGCCUGAUGAGUGCCAUGCCCUCUGUGGACACCUGGGGAGGGGGGUCACCUCCAGCGCCGCCCUGGGACUUCCACUGCACGUGCAAGAGACUUACCCUUUCACACAGAUCACCUGCCUGCCGCAGGGCUGAUGAGGAUGGGUGAGGAGCGCAGCCACUGGGUGUCAUGCACUGUGGGGGUUCUCCCACCUUCUGCCCCUCCUCAGGUUCCUUGCUGCUUCUCUCCUCUCCCAACUGUGGCACGCUGAGGGCUCAGGCACAGGACCGCUCCUCUGGGGCAGCCUCCAAUAACCCUUGGACAACCUCCACUUUUUCAUCUUCAGCCCUGACCACUCCCUGGGGCCCAUAGCCUUACAUCCAUCUGCCCCCAGCCCAAACACUUCUGCAAACACUAGAAAAGGAGGUAGCCCGUGUGCCCUCCUGCACCGCCUCCUCCACUCCUGUCUUGGAGAGGCUUUCCCGUGGGCCGAGCAACCCCCUUACCUUUGGCACUUGCCCUGAUUCUCUGGCCAGCUUCCUACAACCUCUCCUUUUCAGCCACACCCAAGUCCACCUGUUCACAAACACCCUGGGCUGGGCCCUGGCCGAACCCUGGCUUCUACCUACCUGUCUCAGGAAGUGCCUGAGCCUUGCACCUACAGACCCUCCCAGAGAAAGCCCUGGCUUUGCAACCAGCUGUCUUCUCAUGAGACACAGGGCCACAGGAGCACCACGGUGCCCAAAUGGGUCUUGGAGCAUUAGACCAGGGGCUUCAUGCCUGCCCUGGGGACAGGUGGCCAAAGUGGCAUGGGAGAUAGGGAGACAGUGUGGGUGAGCAGGUGGGCAGGAGCUACAGGAGCCUGGGGCCUGUGGAUCACAGACACCGCCAGGCAAGUGCCAGUUCACACAGGUACAGGUGGCUGCAGAGUGCCCAAAGGCCAAGCAGCAGAGUGCCUGGUGUGGACGGGAGAGGAGUGGGGAGGUUGGGCGCAGUGGCUCACGCCUGUAAUCCCAACACUUUGGGAGGCCCAGGCAAGCAGAUCAUGAGGUCAGGAGAUGGAGACCAUCCUGGCCAACAUGGUGAAACCGUCUCUAAUAAAACACAAAAAAUUAGCCAGA